GCAGAGUAAGCCGGGCUGCCGUCUUCUCGCCAUGGGCUCCGGGCCGCGCGGGGCGCUGAGCUUACUGCUCCUGCUGCUGGCCCCGCCGAGCCGCCCGGCCGCAGGUUGCCCGGCGCCCUGUAGCUGCGCGGGGACGCUCGUGGACUGCGGGCGCCGCGGGCUGACUUGGGCCUCGCUGCCGACCGCCUUCCCUGUCGACACAACCGAGCUGGUGCUGACCGGCAACAACCUGACGGCGCUGCCGCCGGGGCUGCUGGACGCGCUGCCCGCGCUGCGCACCGCACACCUGGGCGCCAACCCCUGGCGCUGCGACUGCCGCCUUGUGCCGCUGCGCGCCUGGCUGGCCGGCCGCCCCGAGCGUGCGCCCUACCGCGACCUGCGUUGCGUGGCGCCCCCAGCGCUGCGCGGCCGCCUGCUGCCCUAUCUGGCCGAGGACGAGCUGCGCGCCGCUUGCGCUCCCGGCCCGCUCUGCUGGGGGGCGCUGGCGGCGCAGCUUGCGCUGCUGGGCCUUGGGCUGCUGCACGCGUUGCUGCUGGUGCUGCUGCUGUGCCGCCUGCGGAGGCUGCGGGCCCGGGCCCGCGCUCGCGCCGCAGCCCGGCUGUCGCUGACCGACCCGCUGGUGGCCGAGCGAGCCGGAACCGACGAGUCCUGAGGAGAGAACCGGUGCGUCCUGAGGAGAGAACCGGCGCUGGGCAACACGGGCCUGCAAACUCGACAGGACCCUGCCCGAGGGGCCCUCGCGCCAACCUGGACCGGUCCCCGCCUCCUCCGCUGCCCAAUCUCUCAGACCCACCCCACCUGCAGGCCCAGACCACGUGGGACAGAACUCCUGCCCACCCUACCCCGAGGGAGGCGAACCCGCACUUCCAGGCUUGGGAGGACCAUGGGGCACAAUGCGGUCCAGACCCUGCUGCGUCUCCCUUCCAAACUCUGGUGCUGAAUAAACCCUUCUGAUCUGG